AAAGUUAUGUAUCAUCACUUACAUCCAAAAAACUUUGCUCAAAAAAUGAUAUCAUACUGUGAACAUUUUUUUGAUAGAAUCUUUAAACAUACAACUAAAUAUUUUCUCCAUUCUUCAAUUUACAGUCCCAUUUACUUCCUCUUUAAUCCCAAGUAAAGGUCACUAGAGGAUAAAAUAGAUUUAAUAGAGGGAAUUUGGGGGAUUAAAAAACUAAGAAUUUUUAGCAAUAAGGGAAAUGCAUGGCAUUAUGUACAGGCCAUAACACUCCUAAAAUGGCCUUGUGGGUUGUAUAUGGGCAAAAUGUAUUCAGAGAAAAGAUAAAUCCACUUUUUCUUUCACCUUCAAGCUCCCUUUAGCAUGAAGAGUUCACAAGUGUACAAGGCUGUGUGAGCCUUCAGAAAUGAGAUUUUGAAUAACUGGCCAGGCCAAAGUCAGGUAGAGGAAAAUUUACUAAUCUUUUUGUUCAAUGACUAUUUUCAAUCUUAAGAUGCUUAAAAAGCCACUGCAGGAAGCCACUAUACAGUCCUGGAAGUCUUUCUCCAGACUUCUUAUAUAUGGGAGAGAGAAAUCUAUUUUUCUCUUAUUUAAGCCUGUGUUAUUUUGGGUGUUCUGUCAAGCACAGCAAAUCUAUUCUUAUUAAUACAUUUAUUCAGGAUGUUUGAAGAUAAUAUCACUGCAAACUCUUUGGACUAUUCAGAACAGGAAGAAUAGGGGUAAGUGUUAGUUGUGACCCAAACUCAAUAUAUAUAAUAUCAUCUUCAGUAUUUGAAAUCUAGAGUUCUUCCCAUUUUAUGGGAAGGCAGAGAGACACAAAGGUACAUGUAAGUAAUUUUUCCCUUCAAUUUGUUGUAAAUCCUAUAUUGAGAAUAAACACAGGACUUCUACAGUGAUAAGCAGCAUUAAAUCCAGGAAUGGCCUCUUUCUUGCAGGGCAAUUUUUAUAAGAGACAUUUUUAUGACAUAAUAAGUUAUAAUAGGAAUAAUUUGAUAACUUAUUUCUACUCCAUAGGUGAGACAAAGUUAGAACAUAUAAUGAGGAAAUCAAUAAUGAAUUCAAAGAUGAGAUUUAGAAAAUGUGCCUCAAAACUUUGCAAGGAGUUUGGUUUUGCUGGGCUGCAACAAUGCUGGGGUGCUGUGGGUUAUAGGAGAUGGCACCUUCUCUACCAGACUUUGUAGCUCAGAUUUUUCCCUGUGGGCCCUGAAGGUUGAAAGUGGGGACAGGUUUUAACCAGACUUGAUUUGUAGAGAGAUUUUUAUCAUCAUAACCUCUGAUGCUGGAGAGAAGUGUGUGACUUUUUAUGCCAGACAAUCACUAUUACUGCUUCUACUCACAGAAGGACAUCUGUUUGGAAACCCUGGCCUGACAAUCUUCAUUCCAGUGCCUCUCCCAGAUGUCAUAAGGGUGACAGGUUUUGAGAUAACAUUCUCACCCAGACAGCCACCUCUGAAGUUGGUGGGAAUACUCAUGUGAACUGCUCAGGGAAGUCAGCAAGUCUUACCUCCCGGCAGGCGGCAGCAUGCCAUUGACAGCUCCCGUCCCCUUUCUGCGUUGGUCUCUAGCUCACUCCACUGAGUGCAAAAGCACCAUCUGCGCUCUUCCUUCUAUGAUGAAGACAGAUUCCAUGGUAGUUGCAGUCUUGUGUGGAUUUAAGGCACUGUUAAUGCUGAGGAAUUUUGCUCUAUCAGAUUUUUUUUUUUUUCUGCCGGGAUUAGAAGAUACAGUAGCAGAAGUUUCUGUAUUUGACCUUUGGCAAAGAUACCUAUUUCAGAAUAAGAGAAGAUUUUACAACUUAUUUAUUUAAAAUAAUUAAUACCUAAUUUUUUGUAACAAAUGAAAUAAUCCAAAGAUAUACCAAAAAGUGUAUAAUUUCUUCACUCUACCUCCAUUUCUAUUUCUCUGAAAUAACCAACGUUAGCAGCUUAGAGUGUCCUUUUAUGUAUUUUUCUAGAUUCACAGAAACAUAUUUAUGUAUAUUCAUACAUUUAGAUUUGGUUUGGUUUGGUUUUUUAAACAAAAUGAAAUCAUGUUAUAUACUUUUCCUCGCAACUUAAUUGUUUCACUUAACAAAUGCAUCUAUUGGUCAUUUCUUUUUUUAUUUUUAUUAUUAAUUUUUUUUGAGACAGGAUCUCACUCUGUCGCCUAGGCUGGAGUGCAGUGGCACGAUCAUGGCUCAUUGCAGCCUGAACUCCCGGGAUCAAGUGAUCCUCCUACCUCAGGCCCCCAAGUAGCUGAGACCACAGGCAUAUGCCACCACGCCAGGCUAAUUUUUCUAUUUUUUGUAGAGAUGGGGUUUCACCUUGUUGCCCAGGCUGGUCUGGAACUCCUGAGCUCACAUGAUCCUCCCACCUUGGCCUCCCAAGGUUCUGGGAUUACAGGCGUGGGCCACCGCACCUGGCCUCCAUUGGCCGUUUUCUAAAGUUGAAAACUAAUUUUAGCAUCCCUGUUCACCAGAAGAUGUUAACUAAAAACAUUUAUCAAGAAGAGCUACUACAGUUUCCUUUGGGAUUUUACGAGCAACAUGCAAUAUACCUCCAGGACUUCAGUCAUGUUUAUGGUUCUUAGAAUUUAUGAGGCUUAGGUCUGAAAUACUCCUGAAAAGAUCUGAUAAUUCCUGUGCCUGAGUCACAGGUGCCUUCAGUGAGUCCCAGCCUCUCACACCGUGAUUUGGGGUUAAGGCCAGUGUAACCAUAACUCCACCUCAAGCAGAACUUUAUCUUAGUCAGUUUUGAGAUUAAGUUUGCAAUGACCUACUAGUUUGUUUUCAAUAUUCUUCCUUUUUAAUUGUGUCACUUAAAGCUUAUCACUUGGGAGUUUGAAAAUUGUUCUCCUCUUCCAACUAUUUUAAAAGGAAAAGUUUUAUCCCAGUGACUAAGUGGCUCUGUUAAAUAGCUUAGAAUCAUUCAACUAUUCAGUAUGUUGCAAAGGCUGUGGAUGAAAUAGCAAAUGAGGAUAUUGACUUUUUAAAAGUUCUCAUCAUAGGUGUUUGCCAUCCCCAUUAAGGCCAUCUGAUGGUAGCCUCAAUUCCAAAUCACCGCCACAGACAUCUGUGAAUUUAUGAGUAUAGUGGAUUGUGAUAUAAAAUGAUUUCUAACUGUGGGUCGUGGUCACUGCUCUAGAAAGAAGUGAGCCAUGGCAUGGUGUCAAAAGUCUCCACAAAUAAAAACAUAGAAAAACCUGUCAACCAAGAAAACUACGUUUAAUAGACCUGACGCAGUAAAGUAGACCAUCACUUAGACAAGUUCAUAGUAGUAUCUCAGAAGAAGGAGGGCAGGGAAAGGUAUUUAAACGGAGUGAGUGCUGGACCCUAAUGUAAACCAUGGGCUGCGGGUGAUAAUGAUGUGUCAGUGAUGUUCAUUGGUUGUGACAAAUGUACCACUUGGGUGUGGGAUGUCCAUAGUGUGGGGGAGGCCGUGUCUGUGGCGUGGGACAGGGUAUACGAGAAUCUUCUGUAAUUUCCACUCAAUUUUGCUGUGAACCUUAAACUGCUCUAAAAAUAAAGUUUAAAGUUUAUUAAUUAAAAUUUAAAAAAACAGGGUUUUGUAAGGCAGGGCAGGGAUUGGGCAGAGUAUGCACUGGGCAAAGUUAUGAGAAGCAGUUUUGGAUUAUGAGCCCUGCAAGGUGAGGUCUUGAAGGAAGCCGUUGGACUUGAGAAGUAAGCAAUUUUAGUUGUUCUCCAGUUUUCUCUUCCUAGAGGAAGUAUUUUCUGUAGCAUACAGAAAGAUUACUUUUAUUUGAUCUCAGUAUUUUUUAACAUGGAGACAGGAAAUUUGUCUCAUUUCUCAAUGGGUUUCACCAGAUCUUUUCUGAGGCAACAUUUUCAGGAAAGUCACAGCCCUAAAUCUCAUAGAUAAAUGCUGGCCAAUUGCUGAUUAUGCUGUGGCAACUUUAAGUAACUUUGAAGAAUGUUGGCCCCCAGGGAGUGUCAGGAACCAUUGAGAGCAAGAGUGUGAUUCUUUGCCAUUUUUAAUAGCAGUCAGUUGGCCUCUGCCCUUUAGGAGUUGUUUAGAUUGGCAACUGUGGUGCGUUGGCUCAGUGCCUAGGAAGACUUUGGAAUCUUCCACUAAAAUGGAGUUAACCAGACUUUAAAAGGCUGAGACUCCAUAGAGCUACCUGGUGGUAGUGGAAAUAAAACCCUGGGAGCUGGGCUUUGUUUUUCUUGAUCAUCCACUUUACCUGUAUCAGCUUCUGAACACACUGUUUGAUAUAUUAGUUUCAGGACAUCUAGGGACCGCAGUGCUGGACUAGAAAGGAACACUUGAGCACCACUGGUCAUUAUCAAUGGAAAAAGAUUGUAUCCUGAGAGAAUAGUGGAGAAGGUAAUUUGCCGGGCCUGUGGUACAGGAAAUCCUGCUCACCUGAGAUACUGUGUCACCUGUGAGGGGGCCCUGCCUUCAUCACAAGAGUCGAUGUGCAGUGGGGAUAAAGCCCCUCCUCCGCCCACUCAGAAAGGGGGGACCAUUUCCUGCUACAGAUGUGGUCGCUGGAAUCUCUGGGAGGCGUCCUUCUGCGGCUGGUGUGGAGCCAUGCUCGGCAUUCCUGCUGGCUGUUCUGUUUGCCCUAAAUGUGGGGCCAGCAAUCACCUGUCUGCCCGAUUCUGUGGCUCCUGUGGUAUUUGUGUGAAGUCCCUAGUGAAACUUAGCUUGGACAGAAGCCUGGCUCUAGCUGCUGAGGAACCUCGCCCUUUUUCUGAGCCCCGAUGUGCCUGGCAGUCCCUGAAUAUUCCUUUGCCCAGAUCUGAUGUUGGGACUAAGAGGGACAUAGGAACACAGACUGUUGGCCUCUUCUACCCAUCUGGCAAGCUGCUAGCAAAAAAGGAACAGGAACUAGCCUCUCAAAAGCAGAGGCAGGAGAAAAUGAGUGACCAUAAACCCCUCCUGACAGCCAUCAGCCCAGGAAGAGGGUACUGGAGAAGACAGCUGGAUCACAUCUCUGCUCACCUCAGGUGUUAUGCUCAGAACAACCCUGAAUUCCGGGCCUUGAUUGCAGAACCCAGGAUGGGAAAGCUUAUCUCUGCUACUGUCCACGAAGAUGGUUGUGAAGUUAGCAUCAGACUGAAUUAUAGUCAAGUCUCAAACAAGAACCUUUACCUGAACAAGGCAGUGAAUUUCAGCGAUCACCUUCUGAGCAGUGCUGCCGAGGGUGAUGGGGGGCUGUGCGGCAGCAGGUCCAGCUGGGUGAGUGACUACAGCCAGAGUACCUCAGAUACUAUUGAAAAAAUCAAAAGGAUAAAGAAUUUCAAGACCAAAACUUUUCAAGAAAAGAAGGAGCAGCUUAUACCUGAAAACAGACUCCUGCUGAAGGAAGUCGGACCCACGGGGGAAGGAAGAGUCUCUGUGAUUGAACAGCUGCUGGAUGAGGGAGCAGACCCCAACUGCUGUGAUGAAGACAAUCGACCCGUCAUAACCGUGGCUGUUAUGAAUAAGCACCAUGAAGCGAUUCCAGUUCUCGUGCAGAGAGGAGCAGACAUCGACCAGCAGUGGGGGCCGCUCAGAAAUACAGCUCUUCAUGAAGCAACUCUGCUUGGCCUUGCAGGAAGAGAGAGCACCGCCACUUUACUGGGAUGCAAUGCAAGCAUCCAAAAGAAGAAUGCAGGAGGCCAGACAGCAUACGACCUGGCUCUGAACACUGGAGAUGACCUUGUCACCUCACUCUUUGCUGCCAAGUUUGGCCAAGGGCUUGAGGACCAACUCGCUCAAACUAGGAGCCUCAGCCUGGAUGACUGUUAGCCCUGAGGCCUCCACGGGACUUCAUUUAAGAAUACGUGCAUGGCUGGCACAGUGGCUUACGCCUGUAAUCCCAGCACUUUGGGAGGCUGAGGCUGGCGUAUCACCUGAGGUUGGGAGUUCAAGACCAGCCUGACCAACAUGGAGAAACCCCGUCUCUACUAAAAAUACAAAAUUAGUCGGGCGUAGUGGUGCAUGCCUGUAAUCCCAGUUACUCGAGAGGCUGAGGCAGGAAAAUCGCUUGAACCCGGGAGGCAGAGGUUACAGUGAGCCAAGAUCGCGCCAUCGCACUCCAGCCUGGGCAACAAGAGCAAAACUCCAUCUCAAAAAAAAAAAAGAAUAUGUGCAGCUCUGGCUAUUCUUUAAUCAUGUCUUUCUGAAAUGUGUAUUUGAGAUUAGAAAUUGAGGUUGAGAGGAACUCAGGAGAUUUUUUUUUUAAAUCAUAUGACAGUAUAAGCCAUCAGUACUAAAUGGACAGCUCCCAGUAUACUGUGGACUGUGAUAAACUGAAUGUAUGUUUUUUAAUGGUUUAUUGCUGCAGGUUUUUUGUGUAUUUGAUUUUUAGUUUUUAACUUAUUUUUCAAUAGGUAAUAAUUGCACAUGGUUCAAAGCUAAAAGGUAUGAAGUAUUAUGUAGGGAUACGUCCCUCCCAUUCUGUCCCACAGCCACCACCUCUCUCCUCAGCCAGCAAUGACAUCAGCGUCGACUUGCCUUUCCCGGGGUUGUGCAGAGUUAGAUAUGCACAUACAUGUGGUAUAAGCACAUGUACAGAGGAGUACACAUAGCAUAUAAACAUGUCUGUAGCACAUAUAUAUUCUUUCCCCUCUUUUAAAACAAAUGGUAGCAAACCAACCACACACUGUUCUGUAUCUUGCUCUGUUUGCUUGAUACAUCUUGUAAGUGGCUCCUAAUUACUAUGUAAAGAUUGACCUUAUUUAAAUUUUUUUAUGUUGAAAUCAUCAAUAUUCCCAUCAUUAUGGUGUGUUCUUUGAUUGACAAAUCAGCUCUCAAUAAACCACUUAUAAGAAUGUGUAA